CUCCCCACCGCGGUGACUCUCGGAGCGGGAGGCGGAGGCUGAGGCGGCCGCUCCUGCUGCUGCUACUGCCGCCGCCGCAGCGGCUGCUCGGGCUGAGCACGCCCCGGAACAGGCCGCCGCGCGCUGCGCGCCGGACCCGCUGCCCCUGCCGGCCCGGCCGGGUCGGGCGGCCCAGAUGGUUCAGGAAAAGCAGCAGUGUGCGUGUACCUUGACAUAUACCCACAGCACAGAGCCAUAAAACAUAUAUAGCAAAAUGUGAACAGUGGGACUCCAGGAGCAAGAGAGAAAACCUCCACCAGCACGUCCCCUUGGUUAGAACAGUAGAGCCUGAAGACAUAGCCCAGGAUCUUCAGUGUUCUGGGGCAGCCAAGGAAACUUCCUCAGGCUCCACAUGCCUUCCUGUUUGCAUUGUUUUCAGCUGAAUUUCAAGAGGCUGUCAGAGCAGGCCUGCCAGGCUUGUGAGGGCUGACUGACUCUGCCACUCUGUGCCUGGACUUAGAAAAUGCUGUGGUGACAACAGUAAUUAUUCUUCGGUAGCAUCACCUGGCUUCAGGGAGCAGGAAGGAGCUUUGCAUCAGGUUUGAAUUGGGGUUGGUGACCUCAAGACACAUUCCCCAUCCCAGGCUUAUCCCCUAAGAAUGGGGCUGUGGCCUGCAAAUGCCAUGCCUCACUAGGAGGCCUGUUUUGUCCUAGCUCUGCUGGUGGAGUGCGGUUCGGGAAUACCGAGCGUGGCUGUGGAUGGAGGAGGCUGCAACGUGGAAUAUAUUAAUUAAGGCGGUUGCUCCUGAGGCCUGAGAGUCUGGGAGGUUGUUGCAGUUUAAUUACUGAGAGUGGAGCGUGUGGAAAUUCCCUCUGGCACUCCCUUUUUUGAUGUCGCUAGAGGACCUGAGGUGCUACCUUGUGUGGGACUCUAGCAGGAGCUGCGGCAGGCCUCUGCCCCCCGUCCCCCUCGCUGGCUCAGAGUGACUUUUUACCCAGGUACUUGUAUACUGGAGAGCAACAGGGCAGAGCGGUUGAGACCUUGAACAAUCUGGGUUCCAUCCUGCUCCGAUGUGGACUAGCUGGGCCAUGACAGGGACCGACAGACUUGACAACGGUGACAGCACUGGGGCGGCACCUUCCUACUUCUGCCCAGCCACAGCCCUCCCCUCACAGUUGAGCACCUGUUUGCCUGAAGUUAAUUUCCAGAAGCAGGAGUCCCCAGAGCCAGGCAGGGGGAUGAACCGCGAGGGAGCUCCCGGGAAGAGUCCGGAGGAGAUGUACAUUCAGCAGAAGGUCCGAGUGCUGCUCAUGCUGCGGAAGAUGGGAUCAAACCUGACAGCCAGCGAGGAGGAGUUCCUGCGCACCUAUGCAGGGGUGGUCAACAGCCAGCUCAGCCAGCUGCCUCCGCACUCCAUCGACCAGGGUGCAGAGGACGUGGUGAUGGCGUUUUCCAGGUCGGAGACGGAAGACCGGAGGCAGUAGCUGCAAAGCCCUUGGAACACCCUGGAUGCUGUUGAGGGCCAAGAGAUCUGUGUGGCUCCUGGGCCGGCUGAGUGGCAGCAGCCCCCCUUGCCCCACCUCCCCCUUCCCCUACCCAACCCUGCCCUGCCCCACCCCACCUCACAGCUACUCAGUGGGGCUGGCAUCAAGGGAGACACCAGUGGUGCGUUUAUAAUUGGCUUAAAGGGAUGGACUUGUGAUUGGCUGCAGGAAGAAACUUUUUUAUUUUUUAAAUCUUGACCAACAGAAACCUUUUAUUUUUAUUUCUGACUCUUAUUUUUUAAAAAAUUUGCGCCUCGGUAUCUGGCUUCCCUGGAAGCUCUCCGAGCUCUGGUGCUUUAGUUAGGUCAUUUUUUUAGAAAUGUGAAGAGGUCUGAUUGGCUGCUUAAACUGGAAAGGAUCUGUGAUUGGCUGGUUAAUGGGAAACGGUUUUUUUCUUUGGCUGCAGGUGUUCUGCUGAUAUCAACAGCUUCCCUAUUUUGAAUGCAGAAAACAGGGUCUGGGACAUUAGUCGUUAUAUUUGACUUGAAAAGAAAGAAACCAAGUGCGCUUUGCAAUAUUUAUUACACAAAGAACUUGCUGCUGCCUUCACAUUUGGGGUUUGUGUUUGAUUGGCUUUCGAUGCGUGUGUUUGGUUUCCCAUUGGUUCACCUGUGACUCCUGUUGCCAUGGAUUCACCCCCCUCUGCUGCCGGCUCUGGGCCUGAGGGUCCACCUGGAGAGUACAUUUGCUUUAAUGAGUGCACCUGCCUCCACCAGCAAGGGGACCCCGAGAACCCUGAGCAGGGUCCACAGCUGGAAAGUUGGGCCCCUGAGGAGCUUUGUGUCGUCUUGAACGAGCAGCCCAGGGCCUAGAGGUAACCGUUAGGCGGGAUUUAUGUGCACUGCCUGCAUGAGCUGGCAACCAGCCAGCGUCCCUUGGUGAGAAAGGGAUUGCUGAGGCACCGUCCAGGCCCCACCGGCCAGGCCGCGCCCAGCAGAGGCGUACUACCCAGCUCUGUCCUCUUGGCCAUCCUUCUGUGUACCACUUCCUGAGGCCUCAUUUUGGGGGUCAUCUUGGAAAGGGGAGGAGCUUCUCCCAGUGUGAGACCCCAAAGACUCUGGAGGUCAUCUGGCGGAGGUCUCUGGGAGCCCAGAACCCACAUAAAAGCCCCAGCUUGGCUCACAAGGCCCAGGAGACCUCCAGCUAAACACCAACCCCUGACCUACCCCAGCCAGGCUCCUACCUGUCUGCUGCCAGCACAGUAGGUCCCGGCCAGCUCUGGAGUUCUCUCAUCGGAGGCCCAUGCCCUCCACUCCACUGCCUUUGGAAGGGUCUCUCUCCAGGUCAGCCUGGAAGGGACAGUAUCGUUUGUUUAUGAAAUGCCACUGGGACAGCUGGCUGGGCCUUCACCAAGCAAGUCCCUUCAGACUGGCCCUUAAGCCAAACUCAGGCCCAGAAUUGCAGUUCAGAAUGGCAGUCCUGGAGGCAGGGGGUGAGGGGCAGGUCUAGUGUUCCUGCACCAAACCUAAGUCCUUCCACCUGCCACCCCCUUCCCUGGGAGGGAGGUGGUCCUCCUAUCUCCCUGGCUCACUGGCAGGUGUGGGAUCUGGGGAGAGCGGCUGGAGAAAGAUGCAGUCCUCAGGAAGGGGGCCGCCACCCUCCCCUAUGCUGGUAGAUGCUGAGGCCCCUAGGUGCCCAGGGCCAGUGGGACCCUCUCAGAACCAAAUCUUUCCCCUUUCUCGGGGCUUGGGGCUCGGGCCGUAGGGGCUCCUGAGUGUCAUGAAGUGCACAGGAGCCAAAUGACCGAGCCCUGGAGAGCCCCAUGGUGGGUAGGUGGUUCGUGCUGUGCUCUGGCACCAUCAGCCUGUUCCAGAAGGAGGAUUCGAGCAUCAGGCUAAGACCCUGUGUCCUCCACCAUGCACUCACCCCUAGCCCUGGUUAGCUGACAGUCAGCUGUGGGGAACACAGCUACAACCCUACCCUGGCAGGGACCUGAGAGCAUCUCAGGAGGGGCAGCGCAUGUGUGCAUGUGCUGUGUGAGUGAGCACACCCGUGUGCACACUCAUACACAUGUGCACACACACGCACUCUCCCCGCUCAGGGGCCUGGAGGUCUGGCUGAGCCCCUGGGGAAAGGUGAGUUCUUUCAUCUCCCUCCUCCAGGUCGGAGUGCCUGGAGUCAGGUGUCGAGGCCACAUUGCUGGCUGCCCCCUCUUUGUAGCUCCUAUAAAGGGCCCACACCUGGUGGAUACCUGGUUGAGUGUGUGGUCUCUGCCCCAGCCUGUCCUUGUCACGAUCACAGGCCUUGCUUUUGUAACAAUGAUGACCCCGGCCUGUCUCAUCUUCUGAAGAGGAAAAGUCAAAGUGUUGCUGUGGCUCCAUAUUUCAACUAAAAAUAUAUCUGUUGGAGAAAGAAAUUAACAAUAAAGAAUUUUCAUAGGUU